AGGAACCGCGGAAACUGGAGAGGUGGCACCCCAGCGAGGGCCACCAUGGGGGACCAGAGGCCGCAGGACCGGCCCAGUUCCCCGGGCAUGGACUCCACGCCCUGGUACUGUGACAAACCGCCUUCCAAGUACUUCGCGAAGCGCAAGCACAGGCGCCUGAGGUUCCCGCCUGUGGACACCCAGAACUGGGUAUUUGUGACGGAGGGCAUGGACGACUUCCGCUACGGCUGUCAGUCUCCUGAAGAUACGCUUGUUUGUCGCCGUGACGAGUUUUUACUCCCCAAAAUAUCUCUCAGAGGUCCCCAAGCUGACCCCAAAAGCAGGAAGAAAAAGCUGCUCAAGAAAGCGGCCCUGUUUUCCAAGCUCUCGCCAGCACAGCCAGCACGGAAGGCGUUCGUAGAGGAAGUGGAAGCCCAGCUGAUGACCAAGCAUCCCUUGGCCAUGUACCCCAAUCUGGGAGAAGAUAUGCCUCCAGAUCUCCUACUACAGGUACUGAAACCGCUGGACCCUGAGAGGAAGCUGGAGGACGCAGGCUCUUGUGAGGGCCAGGAGAAGACAACUGACGAACCCACGGAGCCUGGUAAAUACCCCUGUGGGGAAUUCUCCCCUCGGCCUCCCGAGACUCGGGUGUCCUGUCUCCCCCCGGAGCCUCCCAAGACUCCGGUGUCCAGUCUCCGCCCGGAGCCUCCAGAGACUGGAGUGUCCCAUCUCCGCCCACAGCCUCCCAAGACUCAGGUGUCCAGUCUCCACCUGGAGCCUCCAGAGACUGGAGUGUCCCAUCUCCGCCCAGAGCCUCCCAAGACUCAGGUGUCCAGUCUCCACCUGGAGCCUCCCGAGACUGGAGUGUCCCAUCUCUACCUGGAGCCUCCUGGGACUGGAGUGUCUCAUCUCUGCCCAGAGCCUCCCAAGACUCGCGUAUCUCAUCUCCAUCGGGAGCCUCCUGAGACUGGAGUGCCUGAUCUCUGCCUGGAGCCUCCCAAGUCACGCGUAUCUCAUCUCCGCCCAGAGCCUUCUGAGACUGGAGUGUCCCAUCUCCACCCAGAGCCUCCCAAGACUCUGGUGUCCAGUCUCCACCCAGAGCCUCCCGAGACUGGAGUGUCCCAUCUCUGCCCGGAACCUCCAGAGACUCGCGUAUCUCCUCUCCGCCAGCUGCCUCCCGAGGCUGGAGUGUCCCAUCUCUGCCCGGAACCUCCCAAGACUCGCGUACCUCCUCUCCGCCCAGAGACCCCCAAGAAUGGAGUGUCUCCUCUCUUCCCGGAGCCUCCCAAGACUCGCAUAUCUAAUCUCCGCUCGGAGCCUCCCAAGAUUGGAGUGUCCCAUCUCUGCCUGGAGCCUCCCAAGACUCGCGGAUCUCAUCUCCGCCCGGAACCUCCUGAGACUGGAGUGUCCCAUCUCCGCCCAGAGCCUCCCAAGACUCGGGUGUCCAGUCUCCACCUGGAGCCUCCUGAGACUGGAGUGUCCCAUCUCUGCCCGGAGCCUCCAGAGAAGGACGUAUCUCAUCUCCGCCCAGAGCCUCCCGACACUGGAGUGUCCCAUCUCUGCCCAGAGCCCCCCAAGACACGCGUAUCUCAUCUCCGCCCAGAGCCUUCUGAGACUGGAGUGUCCCAUCUCCGCCCAGAGCCUCCCAAGAUUCUGGUGUCCAGUCUCCACCAGGCACCUCCUGAGAGUAGCGUAUCUCAUCUCCGCCCAGAGCCUCCUGAGACUGGAGUGUCCCAUCUCCGCCCAGAGCCUCCCAAGACUCGGAUGUACAGUCUCCGCCCGGAGCCUCCCGAUACUGGAGUGUCCCAUCUCUGCCCAGAGCCUCCCAAGACUCGGGUGUCCAGUCUCCCCCCGGAGCCCCCCGAGACUGGAGUGUCCCAUCUCUGCCCGGAGCCUCCAGAGACUCGCGUAUCUCAUCUCCGCCCAGAGCCUCCUGAGACUGGAGUGUCCCAUCUCCGCCCAGAGCCUCCCAAGACUCGGAUGUACAGUCUCCGCCCGGAGCCUCCCAAUACUGGAGUGUCCCAUCUCUGCCCAGAGCCUCCCAAGACUCGGGUGUCCAGUCUCCCCCCGGAGCCCCCCGAGACUGGAGUGUCCCAUCUCUGCCCGGAGCCUCCAGAGACUCGCGUAUCUCAUCUCCGCCCAGAGCCUCCUGAGACUGGAGUGUCCCGUCUCCACCCAGAGCCUCCCAAGACUCGGGUGUCCAGUCUCCACGCGGAGCCUCCUGAGAGUCGCGUAUCUCAUCUCUGCCCGGAGCCUCCUGAGACUGGAGUGUCCCAUCUCCGCCCAGAGCCUCCCAAGCCUCGGGUUUCCAGUCUCCGCCCAGAGCCUCUUGAGACUCGCGUAUCUCAUCUCCGCCCGGAGCCUCCUGAGACUGGAGUGUCCCAUCUCCACCCAGAGCUUCCCAAGCCUCGGGUAUCCAGUCUCCACCUGGAGCCUCCCAAGACUCGUCGAGUGUCCAGUCUCCGCCUGGAGCCUCCCAAGACUGGUCGGGUGUCCAGUCUCUGCCCGGAGCCUACCAAGACCGGAGCGUCCCAUCUAAAAGAACUGUUUCAGGAAGGUACAUCAAGCACAAUGGAGUGUGUUUCUGACUCUCUUCAACGUAGACACACAUCGAGAAAACUCCGUGACUUCAAGUGGGCUGGAGACCUAGGAGUUAAUGAAGAAUCCAUCAGCAGUCUGUUUGACUUUACCCCUGAGUGCAGAGCAACCUAUCAAGACCAAAAGAAUAAGAAGGCAAACGAGUGUUCCUCAGGGCUGAAGUACAGCAUGGAGCUAGACGAAAUGGAUGAGGUCAAAUUCUUCUCACAGGAAAAAGACUUGGACGGGAAAAUCCAGAAUGCACCAAAUUCUCAUAGUGCACAGCAUGUGAAGAUGGGGUAUGGAGCAUGGUACCUCAAGCCUAAGUUGGGGAAAAAGCUAAGAAGUGAUGAACCUUUGAUUGACCCCAAGCUCGUACUUGAAAAGCCUGAUGAACCCGACAUUCUUGACGGUCUUUAUGGACCAAUCGCCUUUAAGGAUUUCAUUCUAAGCAAGGGCUAUGAAAUGCCUGGCAUCAUUCAAAGGCUGUUUGCCAGGAGGGGAUGGACUUAUGACUCUGUUAAGACUCCUAUUCAACGUGCAAUGCAAGUUUACAAGUACAAAGAAGACGUCACAGAUGCAUCGGAAGAAGAUUAGAUGGUUUUGAAUUUACUAGUUAAUUGGGUAUUUCUUGCUCUCAUUUUAAACAUCAGUCAGAAUUUAUGAUGACUGGCCCCAGGAAUGUACAACGUUGGCAACAUCUGUAAAUUCAAUACCUAAUGUUUAUAAAUAUUUCUUAAUGA